ACCUGGGUCAGCCCUGAGCCCUCGAGCAGGGCGGAUCGGCCGCUGCCUGCUUAAAGCUGGGGCCGCCAGGAGUGCGAUCGCCUGCGGAUCUGCAGCUGGGCACCGGCCGCAACGCCCGCCCCGCGACGGCAGGGCUGGGAAUGGGGGGGACCAAGCACUUCGCAGGGUGACCCGGGGAGAUCUGUGAGCCAGUGGCCUCAGCGUUGAAUGAGAGCUCUCUCCCGGGUCCGCGCUCGCAGGGACUGAAGGGACUCCUGAAUGUCCGCGGGACGUGUCGCGGCGGCGCCCAGCACGGAGGAGGCAGGCAGGGAGGGAUUCCCACCCAGUGCCACGUGAGAACACAGGCGUGCAUCGCAGACAAGCCACACAGGCCUCGCAGGCUCAGCAUACAUGUCUGCAGCAACACCAUCAGGUACAGAGCCGAGGCCCAGGUAGGCAUGCUCAGCUGCACGCAGGAAGCAAGACACACCCAGACACACACAGGGAAUAAAGGCUCAGGGACCGGCAGUUCUACUCUAGAGCCCACCAGCCUCUCAGAGCCUCCGGUGACUGGCCUGUGUCUCCCCCUGGAUGGACAUGUGGACGGCGCUGCUCAUCCUGCAAGCCUUGUUGCUACCCUCCCUGGCUGAUGGUGCCACCCCUGCCCUGCGCUUUGUAGCCGUGGGUGACUGGGGAGGGGUCCCCAAUGCCCCAUUCCACACGGCCCGGGAAAUGGCCAAUGCCAAGGAGAUCGCUCGGACUGUGCAGAUCCUGGGUGCAGACUUCAUCCUGUCUCUAGGGGACAAUUUUUACUUCACUGGUGUGCAAGACAUCAAUGACAAGAGGUUCCAGGAGACCUUUGAGGACGUAUUCUCUGACCGCUCCCUUCGCAAAGUGCCCUGGUACGUGCUAGCCGGAAACCAUGACCACCUUGGCAAUGUCUCUGCCCAGAUUGCAUACUCUAAGAUCUCCAAGCGCUGGAACUUCCCCAGCCCUUUCUACCGCCUGCACUUCAAGAUCCCACAGACCAAUGUGUCUGUGGCCAUUUUUAUGCUGGACACAGUGACACUAUGUGGCAACUCAGAUGACUUCCUCAGCCAGCAGCCUGAGAGGCCCCGAGACGUGAAGCUGGCCCGCACACAGCUGUCCUGGCUCAAGAAACAGCUGGCGGCGGCCAGGGAGGACUACGUGCUGGUGGCUGGCCACUACCCCGUGUGGUCCAUAGCCGAGCACGGGCCUACCCACUGCCUGGUCAAGCAGCUACGGCCACUGCUGGCCACAUACGGGGUCACUGCCUACCUGUGCGGCCACGAUCACAAUCUGCAGUACCUGCAAGAUGAGAAUGGCGUGGGCUACGUGCUGAGUGGGGCUGGGAAUUUCAUGGACCCCUCAAAGCGGCACCAGCGCAAGGUCCCCAACGGCUAUCUGCGCUUCCACUAUGGGACUGAAGACUCACUGGGUGGCUUUGCCUAUGUGGAGAUCAGCUCCAAAGAGAUGACUGUCACUUACAUCGAGGCCUCGGGCAAGUCCCUCUUUAAGACCAGGCUGCCGAGGCGAGCCAGGCCCUGAACUCCCAUGACUGCCCAGCUCUGAGGCCCGAUCUCCACUGUUGGGUGGGUGGGCCCUGCCGGGACCCUGCUCACAGGCAGGCUUUUCCUCCAACCUGUGGCGCUGCAGCAGGGCAGGAAGGGGAAACACAGCUGAUGAACUGUGGUGCCACAUGACCCUUGUGGCACAGAUGCCCACGUAUGUGAAACACACAUGGACAUGUGUCCCAGCCACAGUGUUAUGCUCUGUGGCUGGCUCACCUUUGCUGAGUUCCGGGGUGCAAUGGGGGAGGGAGGGAGGGAAAGCUUCCUCCUAAAUCAAGCAUCUUUCUGUUACUGAUGUUCAAUAAAAGAAUAGUUGCCAAGGCUGAA